AUGCCUCCGUCCAUGCUGCCAUUUCCACUGGCCUUUCCCACAGGGGAGCCCGGGGGCCCGUAUGACCUACCCCCCAACAUCCCCUGGGUCCCCUCCCCCAUGUCCCAGCAUCCCCCGCGUCCUCUCCUCUGUGUCCGGGCAUCCCCUGCGUCCCCUGCGUCCUCUCCCCUGUGUCCCGGCAUCCCCCGCAUCCUCUGCCCUGUGUCCCGGCAUCCCCCGCAUCCUCUGCCCUGUGUCCCGGCAUCCCCCGCAUGUGUCCCCUGCAUCACCUCCCCUGUGUCCCGGCAUCGUCUGCCCUGUGUCCCCCGCAUCCUCUGCCCUGUGUCCCCCGCAUCCUCUCCCCUGUGUCCCGGCAUCCCCCGCGUCCUCUCCCCUGUGUCCCAGCAUCCCCCGCGUCCUCUCCCCUGUGUCCCGGCAUCCCCCGCGUCCUCUCCCCUGUGUCCCGGCAUCCCCCGCGUCCUCUCCCCUGUGUCCCGGCAUCCCCCGCGUCCUCUCCCCUGUGUCCCGGCAUCCCCCGCAUCCUCUCCCCUGUGUCCCGGCAUCCCCCGCGUCCUCUCCCCUGUGUCCCGGCAUCCCCCGCGUCCUCUCCCCUGUGUCCGGGCAUCCCCUGUGUCCCCCGCAUCCUCUCCCCUGUGUCCCGGCAUCCCCCGCGUCCUCUCCCCUGUGUCCCGGCAUCCCCCGCGUCCUCUCCCCUGUGUCCCGGCAUCCCCCGCGUCCUCUCCCCUGUGUCCCGGCAUCCCCCGCGUCCUCUCCCCUGUGUCCCGGCAUCCCCCGCGUCCUCUCCCCUGUGUCCCGGCAUCCCCCGCGUCCUCUCCCCUGUGUCCCGGCAUCCCCCGCGUCCUCUCCCCUGUGUCCCGGCAUCCCCCGCGUCCUCUCCCCUGUGUCCCGGCAUCCCCCGCGUCCUCUCCCCUGUGUCCCGGCAUCCCCCGCGUCCUCUCCCCUGUGUCCCGGCAUCCCCCGCGUCCUCUCCCCUGUGUCCCGGCAUCCCCCGCGUCCUCUCCCCUGUGUCCCGGCAUCCCCCGCGUCCUCUCCCCUGUGUCCCGGCAUCCCCCGCGUCCUCUCCCCUGUGUCCCGGCAUCCCCCGCGUCCUCUCCCCUGUGUCCGGGCAUCCCCUGUGUCCCCCGCAUCCUCUCCCCUGUGUCCCGGCAUCCCCCGCGUCCUCUCCCCUGUGUCCCGGCAUCCCCCGCGUCCUCUCCCCUGUGUCCCGGCAUCCCCCGCGUCCUCUCCCCUGUGUCCCGGCAUCCCCCGCGUCCUCUCCCCUGUGUCCCGGCAUCCCCCGCGUCCUCUCCCCUGUGUCCCGGCAUCCCCCGCGUCCUCUCCCCUGUGUCCCGGCAUCCCCCGCGUCCUCUCCCCUGUGUCCCGGCAUCCCCCGCGUCCUCUCCCCUGUGUCCCGGCAUCCCCCGCGUCCUCUCCCCUGUGUCCCGGCAUCCCCCGCGUCCUCUCCCCUGUGUCCCGGCAUCCCCUGUGUCCCCUGCAUCCUCUCCCCUGUGUCCCGGCAUCCCCCGCAUCCUGUCCCCUGUGUCCCUGGCUUUCUCUGUGUCCUCUCCCCUGUGACCCAGCAUCCCCUGUGUCCUUGCUCCUGGACACCAGCCACCAGGGAAAGGCCACACCAGAGUCAGCUUUCCCCGUCACAGAUCAGCUGGCUGGGCUUUUGUGGGUCUAUUCCUGGGCUCCCCGUUUCGUCCCAGUCAUCCAUUUAUCUGUUCUUUCAUUGAUACUGUUACCUGGGAUGAAUGCCUAUGGAACAUAGCUGAAUUUCUACCCUGCGCUAACUCUGCUUAUCUUUAGGAAACAGGACUCCCAGGAUAAAAAGUUCCCUUUCUAACCAGACCAGCUGAGACUGGUUGAAACCAAGAUAGCUGACCGAGAAACUUCAAAAAGACCUUCAGCCUUAUUAUCAUCUCAUUUCCAUGCUCAGUGACACGCCCACAGUGCCAUGAUGGUUGGAAAUCACCAUGACGAUGACUGGAGGAAGGAAGGUCGCGCUCCGGUUCCAGGAAGCUCACUGCCCGCUCCCGGAAAAGACAUGAAUAUUCCUCCCCUUGCUUGGUGUGUCCAACCCUUUCAUGAGACAGUCAGUGUGUGUCAGCCUCCCCACCCCUCCCAGGCUGAGUGGAUUUGUGAGCCGCACUCCCACUUCUCAAUGCCAGGGCCACGGAAUGAAGCCUGCACUGCGGACACUCACUUUCGGUUUCAUGUAUUGGCUUCGUGACACCCCACAGCGAAAGACCCUCUGUUCUGGGGGAAUGACUGUGUUGGUGACAAAACCAUGCUUUCUGGAUCACUGUGGUAUUACGGCAGGGCUUGAAGUCAGGUAUGUGGGUUCUCCAACUCUGUUCUUUUUUCUUCCUCAUGGUGUUGGCUGUCCGAGGACUUUCGCCUUUCCAUAUGAACUUUAGACUCAGGUGGCAUCGCCUGCAGAAUGCCUUGCUGGGAUUGGCCGGGAUUGAACGUUAGACUCAGGUGGCAUCACCUGCAGAAUGCCUUGCUGGGAUUGGCCGGGAUUGAACGUUAGACUCAGGUGGCAUCACCUGCAGAAUGCCUUGCUGGGACUGGCUGGGAUUGAACGUUAGACUCAGGUGGCAUCGCCUGCAGAAUGCCUUGCGGGGAUUGGCUGGGAUUGAACGUUAGACUCAGGUGGCAUCGCCUGCAGAAUGCCUUGAGGGGAUUGGCCGGGAUUGAACGUUAGACUCAGGUGGCAUCGCCUGCAGAAUGCUUUGCUGGGAUUGGCUGGGAUUGAACGUUAGACUCAGGUGGCAUCGCCUGCAGAAUGCCUUGCUGGGAUUGGCCGGGAUUGAACGUUAGACUCAGGUGGCAUCGCCUGCAGAAUGCCUUGCUGGGAUUGGCCGGGAUUGAACGUUAGACUCAGGUGGCAUCACCUGCAGAAUGCCUUGCUGGGAUUGGCUGGGAUUGAACGUUAGACUCAGGUGGCAUCGCCUGCAGAAUGCCUUGCGGGGAUUGGCUGGGAUUGCAGCGAAUCACCUCUUGGCUCUAAUAGCCAAAAUUCAUAGCUGUGCAGAACUCUCUUUGAAAAAAUGGCCAAUGAUUACAUAAGAGUGAAUCCAAUUCCCAUUAACAAAUCUUAAUAUAAUACAUCCAACAAAGCUACGUGUAGAAACUAAGUGACAUCAAACAUAUGCUUGUCGUAAUCACGUGUGUUGAAAACUGUGUUGAAAAGUGCACCAGGUGCCAGUAGGGGCCAAGGGACCUAGGCCCCUUGCCAAGGUCAGCGCAUGCUGACCUGCGCUGGUGGUCGGGUGGAGGGCUCCAUUUGCAAACAGGCGACAGUUGGCUGCCAAUCUUGUUGAUCAUUUAUUUGCUGAUCAAAAAGGAAUUCUGUCAGUACUGUGCACCCUAACACAAUAUUUGGACCUUCAUACAUGUAUUAGUCGGUUUUCCUGCUGCUAAUAAAGACAUACCCAAGACUGGGUAAUUUAUAAAGGAAAGAGGUUUAAUGGACUCACAGUUCCGCAUGGCUGGGGAGGCCUCACAAUCAUGGUGAAUGGCAAAGGAGGAGCAAAGUUGCAUCUUACAUGGCAGCAAGCAAGAGGCCUUGUGCAGGGGAACUCCCAUUUAUAAAACCAUUAGAUCUCAUGAGACUUACUCACUAUCACGAGAACGGCAUGGGAAAUGUCUGCCUCCAUGAUUCAAUUACUUCCCACCAGGUCCCUCCCACAACACAUGGGAAUUAUGGGAGCUACAAUUCAAGAUGAGAUUUGGGUGGGGACUCAGCCAAACCAUAUCGAUACAUAAGCAUUUUACUGGGCUUUGGCUGUAUUAAGGGAUUGAUUGGAGAUUUUAAGAUCAUACAUUAUAAUUUUUCCCAUUUAAAAUAAUGCAAAAUGUGUUCUUCAUUGAUGCUUCCAAGCACAGAUUCUGACAUUUUGCAACAGGAUUCCAAUGUUAAGAGAAAGCUCCGUGUCACUUACUGGUUCUGAUGGGUCAGACCUGGACUCGGGGAAUGGAGGGGCUGGGUUCCUCCUAAACCACAGGGACUGAGGUGGGGUACGAGUGACUACCCAAAAGAACACUGGGGUUCAUUUAGCAACAGGAUGGGAAAUGGAUACUGAAAAGCAAAAUAACAAAUUUUACAAAAAUGUUUUCUGUCCAAGAAUUAAAUAUGUGACACAUCAAUGUGUUCAAUGUCCUUACAUAUUAUGCGUAAGACAUCUGGGCACAGAUAGGAAGGCAGGACAGGUCUGAGCACCUCCCGCCACCUCUCCCCUCCCGGCUCAGGAAAGCUGCUCACAGCUGCAGCCAGCCCGGCCCCCCGCCCUCACCUGCUCCCCCUGCUGUCUCCAGAGUCCCUGGGCUUUCUCCCCCUCCACCUGUUUCCUCUCCUUGGGCUGCCUCUCCCAGGCUAAACAUGCCCGGGGCACAUCAGUGUUGAAAAGAGCUGUUUCUCUGCUGUCCUCACCCCUAAGCUACAGGCUACACCUUGUUUCCCACCCACGGAGAAUCUUCUAGGGAAAUUAGUGCACAGGAUAAGCUUUUAACAGAUUAUCAGAAACGUUUUCAUCCUAGUGUUUCCUGUGACCAUGUGGCCCGCCCAUCCAGGAUGGUCUGCAUCCAGGGAAAGAUGGGGAAGAGGGGAGGGCAGGCCCAGUGGGGGCCUCCCCACCCACAGGCCCCUCCUCCUCCUGAUGGAGCAGCCCCAUCUGCUACAAGCACUCCCCAGGGGUGCGGGGUUCAUGCUUAGAGCAGCAAUCAUUCCUGUUUAUCUGAAAUUCAAAUCUGCCUGGCAUCAGGUACAUUCAUUUACUAACCUGCAGCUCCACCUGGAAUGAUUUGGGACAGCCCUUCCCAUCUCCCUGGGAAGGAUCAGUGGUGUUUGGACAGGCACUUUGCACCCUGGGUGCCUGUGAGGUGGGUUCCCCUUCAAGAAGAGGCCUAACCAGUGCUCCUGCUCCCUGGGUCGGGUCUCCUCACAGCCCAGGGUCUGGGUGGUCUGCAGGGCAGGCUGUUCUCUGUUCCUCCAGCAAGGAUGACCACUGCAGGUGGGGCUGCAGGGAGGCCAGGUGCUACCAGGUAGAGGCCAGAGCUGGGUCGCUCAGUUCGCUCUGCUCUUGUCCUCAGACCCCGAUGCCAGCUCUAGAAAGAGGGGCCCUUUUGCCUUGGCCUCUCCAUGGGGCACAGGCCUCCCUCCCCACCCCACCACGGCAGUGGGGGCAUGAGCUCCAGGGACACCUGCUUUCCUCACAGCCCUGCCCUGAGGACGCUGAUUUGCCUUCUUGCCACAGGUCCAGAAAAGUCUGGAUUUGAUCCUGGCACCGAGGAGGGUCUCUGUGAGCUUGGACUCCUCUCCUGACAGGGGGAAGGGCAGGGCCAGUGCAUCUCACAGCCAUGGCAGGCUGAUGGGACUGUCACACAGCUUUUUGGCCUUGAACUCAGGGCUUAAUGUUAUCAUAUCACUUAAUACUCCCAGGGACCUGGGUGAGGUACAGUCCCAUUCCCAUUUGACAGAGAGGAGGCUGGGGUGCACUGAGAGGUAAUCAGUGUGCUGGCGACAUUUAACAGCCAGCUCUCCAGAAACAUAAAUCACCCUGAUUUGUGGAGAUUGCCAGGUUCCCAGGCACAAAUAUUCCCAGCACAUCCAAUUUCAAGUGCUAGCAGUUUAACAACUGGCUCAUAAAACCCCUGAAAAUGUGAGAGUCGGCUCCCACAAGCUGCUGUGGGACAGCCCCAGCUCCCUGAUAACCUUCUAGGACCUGCCCUAGUUGGGGAGGAGACGGAUCCAGACCCCAAGGGCCUGGACACCAGGGGGGCUCCACUCAGAUCCUCUGGCCCUCACCAUUCCCAGGACCCCCUCUUGGGCUUCUGUGUUCUUCUCUCUCCAGGGCUGGCUCCUGACACUCCUCUUUAAACAACUGUCCUUAGGCCACUGAGCCCGACCAGCCCCACUGCAGUGAGCCGAAGUGGCCUGGGGGCCAGCCAUGCUGAAGCUGCCUCCUCCCAGCUUGUGGGAUAUGAUUUUGGUGUUUACAGUUUUCAGGAAUUAUAUAAACCAGGUAUGACACAGGCUGAACAUCAGUCAUGGUGAAAUUAUUCACAUCCCAGGAACCUGGCAGGGGCUGUGCUGCUGCUGCCCCUGGGAGUGAGUUGUCCCACACUCAGCAGCUCGCCCUGUCUCAUCCUCCCCACCUAGCGAGGCUUUGACCAGUGACGGGGGUGUGGGAACCUCCAACAGGGCGGCUGAGGCUGGGUUCACGCUCCAGGGCGCCCCUGCAGGACCACAAGGAAGCCAUUGCAGUCAGGAGACCUGGCGCUCAAAGCUUCGCUUAUCCUGACCCUGUGCCUCUCCCCGCUCCCUCCCGGCCCUCCCUUCACGCGUCACCUGUUCCCAAGUCCUCAUCCCAGGAUCUGCUUCCGGGGACCAGGCCUGAUAGGCUCCAAAGCUCUGCUCUUAACCAGCACCGCAACUGGAGGAAAAGCAGGAGGCAUUUGGCUGUUGAUGAUCAUGACAUUUUCAUUAUUCUGUGUGGUUUGGGUUUAUUUUACCCAAGGAGCACAGUCCACAGAAAAUAGAACAUUUCAGGAAUACCAACCAAGCUAAGUAACAUGUUCACAUGAUAUUUAUUAAAACUGUGAUGAAACCGGCUCCACAAACCGUUGAUAGAAGAUGGGCUGUGUAAAACCGGUACUGGGAAAACGGGUUGUCUGUGUGGAGGAAAGUAAGACUGAAUCGCUAACCAAUACUGCAAACAAAGAUGGAGUCUAGAUGGAUUAAAAACCUGAAUAUGAAAAGAGAGAAAAUAUGAAAACAUAUAGAGUCUUUGGGAACUUGUGCCUGGGAACAAUUUUUUAAACACAUUUGGAAAGCAUAAACCAUAGAAAAAUGAUUAGUUUUGUCACAUCAAAACAAAGGAUGCCUGCUUAAUGAAGAAGACCAUGAACAAAAUCAUUAGACGACUGGCAAAAUGGGAAAAGAGAUUUGCAAAGUUUAAAACUGGAACGUGAUCAGUGUGUCAAAUAUACAAUGUAACUUUGUAAAUCAACAAGGAAACAAGGAGAAAUCCCAAAGAAUGGACAGAGCGAUGUGAGCAGGCAACACCCAGGAGAGGAAAUCCCAACAGGCCAAGAUGCCACACCCAGGCUGUCUCCUGUCACUCCUGGCGGUGAUUAGGAAGCUGGCGGCUCCCAGCCUGGGCAGGGACGCAGGGAUGUCCUGCAGGUGGGGGUGGACGGAGGGCCCUGGACCCAGCGGUCCCACCUCAAGUAGACACCCAGGGAGGUGCUGACCCAGGCCCACAGAUGACCUCUGAGGCCCACAGAUGACCUCUGAGCCUGUCUGUGGGGGCCGGGAGGGGCACAGGACCUGGGUGGGUGUCCCUGGGAGAACAGAGAGGAAAAUGGGGUGGGCGCACACGGAGAACCAUGCAGCAAUGAGACAGCAUGAGCUGGUGCACACGGAGCGAUAUGAGAGCAUCUUUAAAACAUGAUUAUUUGUAAAAGUUUACAAAUACACAGAAUGAAAUUAAUCACAUGAGACCAUUGACGUUCAUGCCCGGAAACAGCAAUGGGCACUCUCCAAGAACACGUCCCAAUAAAAAGAUCGUCAUUA